GGGUGGGAAGAAGGUGGGCCUCGAGCAAAGCCGCUAGAGGUGGGGUGCGGGUGGUCGGCCUCAGGCGAGCCCCGGGGCACAGCCCGGGGCGGGAGGCGGAGCUUGGCGGCCGAGAUCUCCGCGCUGCAGUUAGCCCCGCCGAGCGCCAGGAGCUGCGGGUAGGAGGGGCGAGAGAAAGGAUGGGGGUACAGAACCGGAAGAAACGAAGGGCUCGUCCGCUUCGGCUUGUCCUAAUUUGGUGCCCAAUCUGAAGCUGGGCUGUACCAUUGCAUACCUGGGGGAGGCUGUGGCAAAGGUGACAAGAAGGCCGAAGGCACAAAGGGAAGCUGCACCCAUUCCUGGAGGAGCUUAAAUAGUGACUCGAGUGCAAGAAUUUAAAAAUACCGAGACAGCCCUAGGUGGAAAACUUCCGGAAGGCCCAAGCGUUCGUAAGGGCUCUCUACCCCGCUCGGAGCAUAGAUGGUACCGUCCGGAAGUCCGGGCGGAGACCGUAGCUGCGCUUCUCGCGAAAGGGCAGGCAUCGCGGGGCUGGCCACUUCCGUACUUCCGCUUUCCGGCCCAGCCAGCGCCCGCGAUGACUGCCACUCUCCGCCCCUACCUGAGUGCCGUGCGGGCCACAUUGCAGGCUGCCCUCUGCCUGGAGAACUUCUCCUCCCAGGUUGUGGAACGACACAACAAGCCGGAAGUGGAAGUCAGGAGUAGCAAAGAGCUCCUGUUACAACCUGUGACCAUCAGCAGGAAUGAGAAGGAAAAGGUUCUGAUUGAGGGCUCCAUCAACUCUGUCCGGGUCAGCAUUGCUGUGAAACAGGCUGAUGAGAUCGAGAAGAUUUUGUGCCACAAGUUCAUGCGCUUCAUGAUGAUGCGAGCAGAGAACUUCUUUAUCCUUCGAAGGAAGCCUGUGGAGCAGAAGAAGAUCUUUACAAUCCAAGGCUGCUACCCGGUGAUCCGGUGUCUCUUGCGCCGGAGGGGCUGGGUGGAGAAGAAGAUGGUCCAUCGCUCAGGCCCCACCCUGCUGCCACCCCAGAAGGAUCUGGAUAGCUCAGCGAUGGGUGACAGUGACACCACUGAGGAUGAGGAUGAAGAUGAGGACGAGGAGUUCCAGCCAUCACAGCUGUUCGACUUCGAUGAUUUACUGAAAUUUGAUGACCUAGAUGGAACACAUGCUCUGAUGGUGGGUCUAUGUCUCAAUCUCCGGAAUUUGCCGUGGUUUGAUGAGGUUGAUGCCAACUCCUUCUUCCCACGCUGCUACUGCCUGGGGGCUGAGGAUGACAAAAAAGCCUUCAUAGGAGACAAGCAGCCCAAGAAACAGGAGAAAAACCCAGUGUUGGUGUCCCCAGAGUUUGUGGAUGAAGCUCUGUGUGCGUGCGAGGAGUACCUUAGCAACUUGGCCCACAUGGACAUCGACAAGGACCUGGAGGCCCCGCUGUACCUCACCCCCGAGGGCUGGUCCCUCUUCCUCCAGCGCUACUACCAAGUGGUCCACGAAGGGGCAGAACUCAGGCACCUCGACACUCAGGUCCAGCGCUGUGAGGACAUCCUGCAGCAGCUGCAGGCCGUGGUACCCCAGAUAGACAUGGAAGGGGAUCGCAACAUCUGGAUCGUGAAGCCAGGAGCCAAGUCCCGCGGACGAGGCAUCAUGUGCAUGGACCACCUGGAGGAGAUGCUGAAGCUGGUGAACGGCAACCCCGUGGUGAUGAAGGACGGCAAGUGGGUGGUGCAGAAGUAUAUUGAGCGGCCCCUCCUCAUCUUUGGCACCAAGUUUGACCUCAGACAGUGGUUCCUGGUAACUGACUGGAACCCACUUACCGUGUGGUUCUACCGCGACAGCUAUAUCCGCUUUUCCACGCAGCCCUUCUCCCUGAAGAACCUGGACAACUCAGUGCACCUGUGCAACAACUCCAUCCAGAAGCACCUGGAGAACUCAUGCCAUCGGCAUCCACUGCUUCCGCCAGACAACAUGUGGUCUAGCCAGAGGUUCCAGGCCCACCUGCAGGAGAUGGGUGCCCCAAAUGCUUGGUCCACCAUCAUCGUGCCUGGCAUGAAGGAUGCUGUGAUCCACGCACUUCAGACCUCCCAGGACACCGUGCAGUGUCGGAAGGCCAGCUUUGAGCUCUAUGGCGCUGACUUCGUGUUCGGGGAGGACUUCCAGCCCUGGCUGAUUGAGAUCAACGCCAGCCCCACGAUGGCACCCUCCACAGCAGUCACUGCCCGGCUCUGUGCUGGCGUGCAAGCUGACACCCUGCGCGUGGUCAUUGACCGGAUGCUGGACCGCAACUGUGACACAGGAGCCUUUGAGCUCAUCUAUAAGCAGCCCGUCACCACUUCCCCAGCCUCCACACCAAGGCCCAGCUGCCUUCUCCCCAUGUACUCCGACACCAGGGCCAGGUCCUCAGACGACAGCACAGCAAGCUGGUGGGCACUAAGGCCCUGUCGACCACAGGCAAGGCCUUGAGGACUCUACCCACGGCUAAGGUCUUCAUUUCCCUCCCACCGAACCUUGAUUUCAAGGUGGCACCCAGCAUCCUGAAGCCAAGAAAGGUGGGCCUCGACCUGUGACUCACACCCAGUGGACAGUGCUGAGCACGGGGUCAGGGCUGGAGGGCACAGGCAGAGGGCAGCUCCCAGGCUGGCUGGCACCCCAAGGGAAGAGCUGGUCUCCCUCAGAAGCCCCUUCCUCCACAGACUUCUGAUCAUCUCCCUCUUCUCCCCUCCUUUCACACCGAGGCUCCUGCUCUCCUGUGCCUCCGAGGCCCCCAGCUGGAAGUGCCUUGUUGCCUCUGCCCUUUGAAGUCGGAACAAUUCCUAGCACCUGUCGGAAGGUCAAGGCCAAAGGCAAAUUCAAGGCCAGACUGUGACAAACCCAGGGCUGAGGCCUGCCCCAUGAAGAGGCUGAGCCCCCUGAAACCCCUGCCCCUUGUUGGUACAUUCCAGAGGCGCAGGGGCCUGGGGGAUAUGAAGCUAGGGAAGCCCCUGCUUCGAUUCCCCACUGCCCUUGUCCUGGAUCCAACACCAAAUAAAAAGAAACAAGUGAAGUAUUUGGGGCUUGACUCCAUUGCUGUUGGAGGGUCAAGAGUGGAUGGGGCGAGGCCGUGUACCCCAGGGUCCACAGCAAGAGCCUGAGGCCAUCAGCAGCUCCUCCGUGCAGCGAGGCCCAGAAUUCCCACCUAAGGACAGACAUGGGGCUUCCUAUUUAGGGACUCCCCCAGCAUCUCCGAUCCAGGGGUGGGGAGCGUGAGCCUUCACUUUACAGAUGAAGAAACUGAGUCUGAAAGAGGAGGCAUGGCUUACCCAAGAUCACGUGGCAGUGAGUCGACGCAGGGACAUAUUGCCAGAACUGCCGAGCACUGGGAGCCCCCCAACCCCAGAGAACAAGCCAAGCUAGCAGAAUGACACCUACCGGGCAUAGGAACGUUAAUGCCAUGAGACAGGGGAAGGAAUUGGCCUUGCCUAAACCUCAGCCCUUCUGCAGAGGGCAUGGGUCUAUCCCUUCUUCAGCAAGGGGCCAAGGUCACCUAAAAAUGAAACAUCCAAUAAGCCACACCCACCUGAAGAAAAGUGUGGCACUGCUUAGUUGUAGUGGGUUGAACUGUGGUCCCCUGAAAAGAGAUGUCUACUUGGACCCUGUGAAUGUGACCUUAUGUGGGAAAAGAGUCUUUGUAGCUGGGUAUGGUGGCUCACACCUGUUAUCCCAGCACUUUGAGAGGCCAAGGCAGGAGAUCGCUUGAGCCCGCAAGUUCAAGACCAGUCUGGGCAACAUGGUGAAACCGUUUCUACAGAAAAUUAGCUGGGUGUGGUGGCACACACCUGUAGUCCUAGCUACUCGGGAGGCCUAGGUGGGAGGAUUACCUGAGCCUGGGAAGAUCAAAACUGUGGUGAGCUGUGAUCACGCCACUGCGCUCUGAGCCUGGGAGACAGAGUGAAACCCUAAAUCAAAAAAAAAAAAAAAGGUCUUUGCAGAUGUAAAUAAAUUUAAGAUCUUAAAUGAGA